GGCAGCUCCCCGGCAGCGGCGGUGGAGAGCGCAGCGCGCAGCCCGGUGCAGCCCUGGCUUUCCCCUCGCUGCGCGCCCGCGCCCCCUUUCGCGUCCGCAACCAGAAGCCCAGUGCGGCGCCAGGAGCCGGACCCGCGCCCGCACCGCUCCCGGGACCGCGACCCCGGCCGCCCAGAGAUGACCGCGACCGAAGCCCUCCUGCGCGUCCUCUUGCUCCUGCUGGCUUUCGGCCACAGCACCUAUGGGGCUGAAUGCUUCCCGGCCUGCAACCCCCAAAAUGGAUUCUGCGAGGAUGACAAUGUUUGCAGGUGCCAGCCUGGCUGGCAGGGUCCCCUUUGUGACCAGUGCGUGACCUCUCCCGGCUGCCUUCACGGACUCUGUGGAGAACCCGGGCAGUGCAUUUGCACCGACGGCUGGGACGGGGAGCUCUGUGAUAGAGAUGUUCGGGCCUGCUCCUCGGCCCCCUGUGCCAACAACAGGACCUGCGUGAGCCUGGACGAUGGCCUCUAUGAAUGCUCCUGUGCCCCCGGGUACUCGGGAAAGGACUGCCAGAAAAAGGACGGGCCCUGUGUGAUCAACGGCUCCCCCUGCCAGCACGGAGGCACCUGCGUGGAUGAUGAGGGCCGGGCCUCCCAUGCCUCCUGCCUGUGCCCCCCUGGCUUCUCAGGCAAUUUCUGCGAGAUCGUGGCCAACAGCUGCACCCCCAACCCAUGCGAGAACGACGGCGUCUGCACUGACAUUGGGGGCGACUUCCGCUGCCGGUGCCCAGCCGGCUUCAUCGACAAGACCUGCAGCCGCCCGGUGACCAACUGCGCCAGCAGCCCGUGCCAGAACGGGGGCACCUGCCUGCAGCACACCCAGGUGAGCUACGAGUGUCUGUGCAAGCCCGAGUUCACAGGUCUCACCUGUGUCAAGAAGCGCGCGCUGAGCCCCCAGCAGGUCACCCGUCUGCCCAGCGGCUAUGGGCUGGCCUACCGCCUGACCCCUGGGGUGCACGAGCUGCCGGUGCAGCAGCCGGAGCACCGCAUCCUGAAGGUGUCCAUGAAAGAGCUCAACAAGAAAACCCCUCUCCUCACCGAGGGCCAGGCCAUCUGCUUCACCAUCCUGGGCGUGCUCACCAGCCUGGUGGUGCUGGGCACUGUGGGUAUCGUCUUCCUCAACAAGUGCGAGACCUGGGUGUCCAACCUGCGCUACAACCACAUGCUGCGGAAGAAGAAGAACCUGCUGCUUCAGUACAACAGCGGGGAGGACCUGGCCGUCAACAUCAUCUUCCCCGAGAAGAUCGACAUGACCACCUUCAGCAAGGAGGCCGGCGACGAGGAGAUCUAAGCAGCGUUCCCACAGCCCCCUCUAGAUUCUUGGAGUUCCGCAGAGCUUACUAUACGCGGUCUGUCCUAAUCUUUGUGGUGUUCGCUAUCUCUUGUGUCAAAUCUGGUGAACGCUACGCUUACAUAUAUUGUCUUUGUGCUGCUGUGUGACAAACGCAAUGCAAAAACAAUCCUCUUUCUCUCUCUUAAUGCAUGAUACAGAAUAAUAAUAAGAAUUUCAUCUUUAAAUGAGUAAGAGAAAUAAGUAUGUUAUUCUAAAAUCUAAACUCAAAUGAAAUUUCAAAAAAGACCAAAAAAAAACAAGGCAACAGAACCAGGGCUCAGUGCCGACGCCCCUACCCUGGGGGUCUCGGCCACAUGGUCCUCGUGAAACCGUUACGAGUGCUGUACAUGACCACCCACUGUGCAAAGAGCUACGAUUGCUUUCGUUCGUUAAUUCUCACACACCACAUCCGACUCGCACUCACAUCCAGCUCAACAUCGCUACCUUUAGAUCUUUCCGAUUGAUUUGAGAUUUAGCGGAGUGCAGCGGCUGUGUGUCAGUCAGAGAGAGCCCCAGGUUGGCUGCUGGGGGGCCGGGCCUCUGUGCCAGCCCUGCCACUAACUCGCUGUGUGAUCCUUGGCGAGUCCCUAUCCCAAUCCUGGGCCCACUUUCUCGCCCCUCUCGAGGGAGGGGUUUGAACACCGACCACCAUGGUCCUCUCUGGCUCUAAAACUCUGAAUUAGGAACGAGGGGGUAUGAACCAAAACACUUCCUGACCCCAACAAUUGGGAUCUGAUGAAGACGAAUUCUCAUCCUGGGAUCCGAAAGGUUUUGGCCUAUCCUGGAUGAACGCUUGAUGUUGAAAUUUAUCCUAACUGUGUUUCUCAAAGUGGGGAGCCUCCUGGCCCACUUCCCUUUUGGGAAAAAAUAGCCCCUUUGAGUCAUAAUGUGCCAUCUGGAGUUGCCACUUAGGCAGCCAGCCCUCCCCCACCCCUCUUUGCCCACCCAGAACCCCAACACUAUACCUGCCUCUACCCUAUAGAGACAUCCCUUGAGACUUGAAUGUACUUUGAGCCGCAAGUGCCCCUGGCAGAAUCUGAGCAGCAACACAGCCCUCACCAAGGUUUUCACAGGGAUUAGUGGAAAUUGUCACUUGUGGGGCGCUUACUAGUUUUGUGGCAAAUGUGGUCCAAGACCUGGCCCACACAGCCAUGGGUUUACAUUUGUGUUGCUGAGUUAAUAAUCCUCAGAUCUCAAAAGACCUAGCCAGCUUCUGAAUUUUGAAUUUGACUUUUUUUUUUUUUUUAACAAAGAGCAUCUAUCUUUUUUGCAAAAAUAGAAAGAAAUGGGACAGAGCUCUGUUUAGCUUUUCAGCUUUUGGGGUUGGACAGCUAAACAGCCCUUGGGUACCAGAUAGGAAUAUUUUGCUUCUUAGAUUAUUUGGAUAAGAAUCUAUACUCUUAGCUUUAUUGAGCAUUGCCUGCCGUGUUUACCUUGCUCCAGGUGUUUAUUUCUAAGUCAUCAUCACCUUCGUCAUCUACAGUCAGUCACAUCAGUCACCCACACACAACUCACAGUCACCCAUCCAUUGGUCACCUGCGCCAUCGUCAUGACACAAUAUCGACCUCAUCACCUCAUCGUCCUCCAGCCACUACCCAAGCCCCCUCAUCCUGACUCAAAGCCCGACCAGCAUCUGCCCAAACUCCCAACACCCCACUCUCCCCACCAAGCCAUUGGUCUCCUCACUCCCGGUCCUUUGUCAUCCUGAUUCCAAGCCCCGCCCCACCCUCACCGCCUCCUCCGCAUCAUCUGCACUCUGCAGAGCCCCUCCUACCCGCCUCUGUCCCCACCAGGCCCCUCCCUACCGUCAGCCCUGAGUCCCACAGCACGCGUCCCCAGCCCCUCCCAGCCUCACCCCAAAAACCCUGUCACCCCACCGACCACCAUCAUCACUGGCAAGCCCCUUCCCCUUCUCCAGCUCCCGUCCCCACUACCCCUCCCGUCCCCCAAUCCUUCCCCUCCUGUUAGCCCACCCCUCCUUUCCUAUCACCCCCACCUUUCCCUUCCCAUUCUCCCCACCCUUCCCCUCCGAUCCCACCACCCUUCCCUUCCGAUCCCCGUCAUCCUUCCCCUCUGAUCCCCCACCCUUCCCCUCCUGUCCUCCCCAGCCCUCCCUUCCUAUCACCCUCACCCUUCCCCUCCCGUUCUCCCCACCCUUCCCCUCCUGUCUCCACCAGCCCUCCCUUCCUAUCACCCCCACCCUUCUCCUCCCUUCCCUCACCCCAAACCCCUGGGUCCUCCACCCCAAUCUCUGACAACCGCCCCAAGUCCCUCUUCCUUCCCCACGAAGUCAUUCAUAAGUCACCAUCUCAUCUCAUUUUGAGUUUGUUUUAAGAAAUAAAAAAAUUAAAAAGACAAAAAAAAGAAUUGUUGGCAUGUGUCAGGCGGGCGUCUGGUACCCUGCCUGGCCUCUCUCAGCGUGAGACCUGGACUGAGCCUGCUAACGAUUCUGUUCCUCAGUUUCCCCAAAUAGAAAAUUCUAAGAUUGGUCAGAUGAUCAAAUUAUCUAUGUUUUCGAUCUUGAUGCUAUAGAGAACAGCCAUGUUCCCCUGAUAACAAGAAAAAGACGUCCCACGGUCGAGGUAUCCUUGACCAACUCCCCAUCCAUUCAUUUGUUCACCGUCCACAACCCAUCUGAUCAGGAAGCAUUUCCAGGCACCUGCGGAGCACUAGGCAGUGUGCGGAAGCUGCAGGGCAGGCAGGACGAGGGGGCAGUCUGGAGGGGGGUGGACACACAGCUGUCCCCAGGGAGCCCAGCGCGGUGCCGGUCACAUGCCGUGGGAGUGGAGGGUCUUGAGCAGACGCCUCCCUUGGAGAAGAGCCACCAUCUCACCUUCCCACGCAACAAAUUAUCUAUUACCAGCACCCGAUGAGGCCGUCCCUCCCAAAUUCCACAGUGCCCACCACUCGCACUACCCCCCCCGUGCCACAGAAGCAGUGUCAGCAGCCUCGCCACGGUCUUCACGUCAUGCAGAAAUGGUCAUUCCAUGUUCUAUGGCCACCAGAUUCUGCUGAGAGUGUCGGGAUCCUUGACUGCCCAGCCACACCUUGUGUGUGUCUGGUGUAGUGUGUAGUUUACGAAACAAACGGAAAAGCUCAAAGACAGCGAUCCAAGACAUGAUCAGCAAUUUGGUCCCAAAUUAGGAGAGGAGGAAGAGGAGUAUCAAUUUUGUCACCAAAAUGUUAAAAAAAAUGUCCUUGGCGCUCUUUUUAGCUUUCCCGUUUACUACCAGUCCAGACAUGCAAAAAAACCUUGUUUAUUGAAAAAUAAACAACAAGGGCUAGA